UAAGGGCUGUUUAACCAGCAGGUGGUAAAUUCUGGCAGGAUUGGGUCCUUCCUUUCAGGGCAGCAGGUUCCCUUCUGGCCCAGGGUUGGUCUAGAAAUGUCAUCCAGGAGUUAUGGCCUAGAAUGGGUGCAUUAGGACUCUGCUUGGUGCUUUAUUUUACUGUGGCUGAGCUGGUAUGCAAAUUGCAAGACAAAGCCCUCUUUAUUCACUCUUCCCUCUUUUCCUGGAGCUGUGAGCUGUGCUGCCUGGGAUUGCAGAAGGGGCAGUACAAGCACUCCCUUGGCUACCCAAGCUGGUGUCCCACUGGAUCAUGUGCAUCCCAAGUCCACUGACUCUGAGCCCAGCCCAGCACCAGGACUUGCCCAGUAAUUGCAGUCUAGGCCACAAGAACUAGUUUAUUGAAGACCCUAGAGCUCUUUAGCUUGCAGUGGUGGGACUAGCCAGAACUCAGGUUCUGACCACUGGGAUGGGCGAUUCCUCUCUGGCUAGGGCUCAUCUAAAUGCUCCUUCUGUGGGCACCAGCUGAAUUCUGCCCUGUGUUGCUUGUGGUGUGAAGGGACUCACUGAGUUCCAAUGCAAAGUUCCAUUAUCACUGUGCUCUCUGCUUCCCAAGCACACAGAUUCUCUCUUCCUGUGCCGUGUGGUAUUUCUGUGGGUUGGGGGAAGGGUAGUGUCAGCAAUUCAAGACUGUCUUUCCUACCCUCUUAGGUGCCUCUUUCCUUGAUGUGAUGUUAAAACUAGGUACUGUGAUCAGUCCUGAUUUGUGGUUCUUAAGAAGGUCCUUUUGAAACUCACCCAAUUGUCCCAAAGAGCUGAUGUUUAUGGUUUCUUUUGAAUAAACAUAGAAAUUGACCCUUCUAUUCUUAAAACUAGAGAAAGUUAUAUUUGUCUUAUUGGAGUUCCUUCCUCAGGAAACUGAACCUUAGGCCUCCCAGAUAUUAUCAAGGAACUGAAACUCAGCAGAUCACUGCAUCCAGACAGUGAAAGGCCAGACCCCUCAUUUAUCAUGACUGCUUCCUUACCUCUCCUUAAUUCCUGUUUUCCUGCAUGUAGCUUAUUACUUCCUUGUUAUAUAAGUCCUCAGUUUUAGUUGGUCAGAGAGACAGAUUUGAGACUGAUCUCCCAUCUCUUUGGCUGCAGCACCCAAUAAAGCCUUCUUCCCUGGCAAUACGUGUUGUCUCAGUGAUUGGUUUUCUGUGUGGCAAGCAGCAGGACCUAGAGCAAGCCCCUGGUGUUUUGGUAAUACUUUCUUUUGUGGAUAGUUGUUCAAUUUGGUGUUCCUGUGGGGAGGAUGACUGCUGGAGUGUUCUAGUCGGCCAUCUUGCUCUUUCUCCUCCCCAUUCCAAUAUUUUUGAGAAUUUUUAUUAUGAAUGUAUAUUGAAUUUUGUCAAAUACUUUUUCUACAUCAAUUGCAAUGACUGUGUAAUUUUUCUUCUUUAUCUUGUAAUAUGAUGGAUUACAGAGAUUGUUUUUCAAAUAUUGAACCAGCCUUGCAUCUUUGGGUACAUGCUUCUUUUUAUAUAUUACUGAUUUCUAUUUGCUAACAUUUUGAUAAGGAUUAAUGCCUCUAUAUUUGUGAGGAGUAUUGCUCUGUAGUUUUCUUUUUUGAUACUAUCUUUGGUUUUGGUAUCGAAGUAGUACUAGCUUUAUAAAAUGAAUUGGAAAGUGUUCCCUUCUUUUAUAUUUUAUGGAAGAGAUUGUGUAGAGUUGGUAUUAAUUCCUUAAGCCUUUGAUAGAAUUCUCCAGUGAAAUUAUCUGUACCUGUAGAUUUCCUUUUGGGGAGUUUUAAAAUUAUGAAUUCAAUUUUCUGGGGCUAUUUUGUCAAAUGAUCUAUUUUGUAUUGGAUGAGUUGUGGUUGUUUGUACUUUUCCAGGAAUUGGUCCAUUUUAUCUAAGUUGUCAAAUCUAUGUGUGUAGAAUUGUUCAUAGUAUUACCUUAUCAUUGUUUUGAUAUUUUCAGGGUCUGAAAUGAUUUCCCUUCUUUUAUUACCUGGUAUUGGGCAUUUGUGUCUUUUUUUCUUAUUUAAUUACUUCUCAGUCAUUAUAGAGAUUUGUCAAUAUUACUGAUCUUUUUAAAGAAUGAGCAUUUUGUUUGAUUGAUUUUUCUCUAUCGUUUUUCUGUUUUGAAUUUUAUUGGUUUCUGUUCUUUAGUGGAAGGAAUAAGGAAAAGCAUGCCUACUUAGUCUUCUUGGAAGUGGGAUCCCUCUUGUGUCCUUUUGACAUGCCUAUCAUUUCUGAUAUGCCUAUCAGAAAUUUUUGGCAUAACAAGAUAUUCCAAGUUCAUCUUGUACCUCUCACCCCUGAAGCAUGAAAUUAGUCAUUUCUCCAAAAAGCCCUGGUUUUACUUAGGAUUGAUCUCCAUAGGAUUUUGAAAUGGGUGAGAACUAUAGGUCUGCUCUCCAAUAAAUCUAUUACUACAUUAUAAUGAAAGCAAAUCCCAGACCAAAUUCUGCCACAUAUACAGUAUAUACAUUUAUUAACUAAAUUCUUGUAAUCAAAGUAGCACAUAAAAAACUGUCUUGCAGGCUUGAGAAGUCCUAGCUCUUUAGUCUCCUAGAUGUUUUGAACACUGAUUCCAUGGUAGGUCACUAUAGGUAAACUCCAAUUUUCCAUAGGCAGGGUACUGAUACCACCACUCCUACUCCCAACCUCCACUCCUCAGCCAGCAUCAGGGAGAAAGAAGCUUCCAGAGUCCAUGUUGGCUCAGGACCAAGGAGGAGUUUUAGCUGAGAGCAUAACCCUGUAGGUAGAGUACCUACACAUUGGAUUAUCUCACAAAUUCCUGCAAGGGUGGGGAGUACCCCUAAUAUAUUGACAUAAUCCAUGUAUCUUGAAUGCCUUCAAUUUCACAGUGUUAGACCACUUUUGGUAUUCAUUAUUACUAGUCAAUAGGCUGCUAUUUUAAUCAAGAAUAAGCAAAGCACUCAUUUCUGACAACCCCUUAUAGUAGCUCCUGCUGGCGAAUGGGCUCUCUGAAGAGAAGGACAGCUGACCACCACUGGACAAUGCAAUCUUGAUUAGAAUGCUUGUGGUACCAGGGUGACAGCUUGACCUAAGCAACAUUUAUGUAGAAUAUCCCACUGUAUGUAUCCUAAUCUAUAAUUAGGAGCCCUUUUAGAUAUUUCCAGAGGGAUACCAUUAUUAACAAGUGUUCACUGAGCAAUUGUUACCUGCCUUAUGUUAGAGAAGGCUUGCUAUAAAGAGAGAGCUCUUAGAUCCUGCACUCCAGGACAACAGGGAUGAGGCACCCUGGUCCCCACUGUAUCUCCUAUGCUGACUUCUAGGAUCUCACAAUAAACAGUGCCCGACUGAAGGUGGAAGACAGAAGGAAGGGUGAAUUAGUUAAAGGGAACCCAGGGAACUACUACUCUCAAGAUAAAGAGUGUUAGAAACAGGAGAAAUUGAAUGAAAUGGCUUCCUUGGCAAGUGCUGAAGAUCUUUAAAGCAGCUCUGAGAGGAAAAGAAUUAAGGGCUGAGACAGCCUUCACCUUGCCACCUGUGAUAGUAGCUACGUCUUUUCCUUCCUGUUACCUAAAUCUUAGCCCACUGGGGUGCAUCUAAGAAUCGCUGUCUCCCUUGCCACCUGUCUUUGUCAAUCUGUAUCUCUGUGUCCCCUCCCUCCCUCCUUUCCUUCUCUUCUCCCCACCUUCUGUCCUUAUUGCUCUUUCUUGUCUCUGUCAUUUUGUUUGUGUCUGUUUCUGCUUGUUCCCAUGUCUCUUCAUCUCAGUCUGUCUGUAUUUACCUCUCUGUUUCUGUUUCUCUUUCUCUUUCUGUAUCCAUUGCAUUCACUCUCUGUCUUGCCUUUCCCUCUGUCUGUCUUUAUCAUUUCUGCCUCUGUGUGCCUUUCUGUUUCUGUUUCUCACCCUCGCUUCCUCACCCUGUCUCCCUCCCUCUUCCUGUGUUAUUCAUCUGUCCUCUUUCUCAUUCCCAUCAUGUGUAGCCACUGAGAUGCGUAGACUGGGAUGUAUAUGUUAUUAUCCACCUUGAUUAUAGUUAUUGAUAAUUAUACGUUUCUAAAUACUUGGUACUUUCUUCCCAUGAUAUAGAGGUACACAUUAUAUUCCUCAUCCCACCAGGGUGUCAAAAAAUUAUCCACCCUCAGAGGUUUAUUUCAAGGUACAAAUUACCUGUGCAAAUAGUGACCCUCAGUCUCCAGCAGGUGCUCCAAGAUGUAUCCAGAACAACAUGGGGAGCAGGGCAUGGACUGUCCCUGCUGCACAGUUAGAUGAGAUCCUCAUACUGCCACCCCGUGGCACCUCCACCCUCCCUCAGGGCUCUUUGGGAACUCUGGGGUCAUGAUUUGGGAUCAAUUAUCUUUUAAGCAUUCCAGAUGCUGAACUGGCUGCUUCAGCCUGAGUGGGUUCAUGAUGCUUUGCAAGGGUGGCUGUGGCCUGCCUACUUGUUGGAGGAGUACAGUUGGCAUCACUGACCCACACAACAGGACAGAACUCCACAACCUCCAUGGGAUCCUCAGCUGUGACAAGAUCAUUCCAUACUUUGCACUGAGUUUGUGGUGGUUUUUAAUUGCCAACAGAUCCUACAAAGUCAGUGCAGCAAGCUCUUUUUUCUUCAGUGGUGUAUUUGUUGGAGUUAUCUCUUUUGGUCAGCUUUCAGAUCGCUUCGGAAGGAAAAAAGUCUAUCUCACAGGUUUUGCUCUUGACAUCUUAUUUGCAAUUGCAAAUGGAUUUUCCCCCUCAUAUGAGUUCUUUGCAGUAACUCGCUUCCUGGUGGGCAUGAUGAAUGGAGGGAUGUCGCUGGUGGCCUUUGUCUUGCUUAAUGAAUGUGUGGGCACCGCCUACUGGGCACUUGCAGGAUCGAUUGGCGGCCUGUUCUUUGCAGUUGGCAUUGCCCAAUAUGCCCUGUUAGGAUACUUCAUCCGCUCCUGGAGGACCCUAGCCAUUCUGGUUAACCUGCAGGGAACGGUGGUCUUUCUCUUAUCUUUAUUCAUUCCUGAAUCACCUCGUUGGUUAUACUCCCAGGGUCGACUGAGUGAGGCUGAAGAGGCGCUGUACCUCAUUGCCAAGAGGAACCGCAAACUCAAGUGCACGUUCUCACUAACACACCCAGCCAACAGGAGCUGCAGGGAGACUGGAAGUUUCCUGGAUCUCUUUCGUUACCGGGUCCUGUUAGGACACACUUUGAUCCUGAUGUUCAUCUGGUUUGUGUGCAGCUUGGUGUAUUAUGGCCUAACUCUGAGUGCGGGUGAUCUAGGUGGAAGUAUUUAUGCCAACCUGGCCCUGUCUGGCCUCAUAGAGAUUCCAUCUUACCCUCUCUGUAUCUACUUGAUUAACCAAAAAUGGUUUGGUCGGAAGCGAACAUUAUCAGCAUUUCUGUGCCUAGGAGGACUGGCUUGUCUUAUUGUAAUGUUUCUUCCAGAAAAGAAAGACACAGGUGUGUUUGCAGUGGUGAACAGCCAUUCCUUGUCCUUGCUGGGGAAGCUGACCAUCAGUGCUGCCUUUAACAUUGUUUAUAUCUACACCUCUGAGCUUUACCCUACAGUCAUCAGGAAUGUUGGGCUUGGAACUUGUUCCAUGUUCUCCCGAGUUGGUGGGAUUAUUGCUCCCUUCAUCCCCUCACUGAAAUAUGUGCAAUGGUCUUUACCAUUCAUUGUCUUCGGAGCCACGGGUCUGACCUCCGGCCUCCUGAGUUUGUUAUUGCCGGAGACCCUUAACAGUCCGCUGCUAGAAACAUUCUCCGACCUUCAGGUGUAUUCGUAUCGCAGGCUGGGAGAAGAAGCAUUAUCUUUACAGGCUUUGGACCCCCAACAGUGUGUGGACAAGGAGAGCUCUUUAGGGAGUGAGAGUGAGGAAGAGGAAGAAUUUUAUGAUGCAGAUGAAGAGACUCAGAUGAUCAAGUGAAGAGCCCCAGAUUCCCCCUAAGAAGCAAAGGAUCGUCUUUUAUGCCUCUGGCUAAGGCAGGUUCUUCCAUGACUCCUAAGAGAGUUGUAAAAAUAGAGGCUUGGCUUGAAUGUACAUAGAUGGUACCUGGCAUGGACUGAUGUUUUUAGGCACAGAAGUUGGAGAAGAGAUUUCAUGAAAGACAACAUCACUGCAUUGAGAGAAUAGUUGUUAAUUUGUUUAGAAUUUAAGUUCUACUCAGAAUCAUAACAUCUGGCAGAACAGCCCAAACCCACAUUCCAAAGUGGUAGGCUCAUUUGUUUCUAGAGAUUUCAUCAUGUCGCUUUUCCUUCAUCAUGAUCUAAAUAAAGGCAGAUAUGUAAAAUUUCUCACCAUUUUGGUGGGGUAAGAUAAGCUAUUAUUAAGAUUUAAUCCUUAUACCAUGUUGGACAUUUGCCCCUAUCAGUUGCUCCUCAGGAAUCUUCUGGUACAGGUUAACAUCAGCAUUUUCAUUUUGUGUCCAGGGAAAAGCACCCAGAGGUCAUCUGUGUGUCCCGAGACCCUCCAGCUUUUUCUUAGCUGAUGAAAUAUGAGUCCUCAGCUUGGUUCCCAGCCUGCUGAUUGACUUGGGCUGCUGGUGCCUUGAGUCCCACAGAUGAUUCAUUAGGAAAAGCCAGAUAUACCAAAGCGGUUUACUCAGAGUCAGGGGUGUAGCUCUGGCUGCCUGUCAGCUCCCUUGGAUACUAUAUUGUAUGAUUUCUUCCUUUCCCACUAAUAUGCACAUCCAGAAAAAUUUCCAUCUGAGAUUCUAGUACUUCAAAAUCAUGCAUAGUAAAUGAGAAAGCUUUAAGUAGAGGGCAGUUAAACAGUGACAUGUUGAGCACCUGGAGGAAAAAAAAGGUGCAGUUUUUAAUAAGAGAGAAAAUGAAAUUAUCUUUGAUAAAUUUUUGUUUGUUUUGCUUUCAGCAUUGUGCCAUGAGGGAUUUGGACAAUAUUUAAGAACUUCUUGUCCUAGAUCAGCCCCAAUCUGUUUAAUCAAAAUGGAAGGUUCAGUAAUUUCAUGGGAAACCUUGGUUUUUCAUUAAGUGCUACCAACUUUCAAGUGAAUCUUGUAUUUGAUUUCCUAAAAUCAUGUCUUGAAAACAUGUUUUCUCAUGAAACUUGAAUACUAUCUCAAAUAGGAAUAUAAACCUGGAGUCAACAAGCUUAGGCAGCAUUGAUUUAGGUCACUUUCCCAGUGAGGAAAAUUUCUGUGUUUUCAGAAUUUCCAUUUCUACUAACCUCUUGGAGAAAAAGAAAUUGAAUUAGAGGUAAAUAGAAGACGUCACUGUGGCUGCUUCUGGAAGUGCUGGAAGCAUCACCCCAAUUGGCUCCAAAUACUGUCAUGUUUUCUUGCACACUGACUUCUGGUUUCCACUGUAUCAGUAUGUACCUUUGUAAUUGUUAUUUUUAUGUCUUUUAUGCCCUUGAUUAUUAGUUGGGCUCUUCAUAAACAGAGGCCAUCUCUACUACUGUUUAUUUUUCCCUGCUGUGCCCAGAACAUUGGCGUAGACACAGUAAGAACCUAGUAAAUAUUACUGUUUCUAGCCAUCAGGGAGAUUGUGGAACUCCUCCCAGUAUAAUUUUUACAAACUCCAAGCAAAUCUGACCCAAACUCCCAAAUUGUCAAGUCCUGCUUAACUUUCUCUGGAAAAUAGACCCCUUCUCAACAUCAGAAUAGGAAGAGAGGAAGAACUUACAAAGACACUUAAAAGUUAUUCUUAAAUGGUGGUUGGGCAUUUAAAACAGUGAACUAACAUAUAUAUAAUUUUUGAUUAGUUGGAGCUUUCUUUGUAUUAUAAGAGUAAUAUAUCUCAUUACAGAAAAUUUGGAAACUAUAAAUUUAGAAACGUAUCACCCAUACGUCCAACAUCGAAAGAAAACCAGUGUUAUGACUUUGUUCCAUUUGAAGACUAAUUGGGAGUCCAUCUCUCUAUUGGCACUGGGUUCGAUUGCCUCUGGCUAAUAGAGUUCAAUUAGUUCUAUCCCUGGGUUUCCUUUCUUAGCUAUGGGGUGGAAGAUAGGAGGGGGAGAUCUACAAUUUGAAUAUGUGUUACUUAAUAAGGCUAGGCUGGCCAUCAGUUGCUUAUUUCAGAUGUGUCACUAAAUUUUCCUUCUAGAUGGUCCUUGAGCAAAACUUAAUAAUUACUGUUUUUUAUUUCCACUGCCUUUAUAAAAUCAAAAUUUUCUCCUUUUGAUAAAAACUGUUGAAUACUAUUGAUGUAGAGAAUGUGUAUAUGUGUAUAUUUGCAUUGAUUAAAUUAUUGGAAAACUUUUCAUUGACAGGUAAUGUAUUUUGGUUGUGCGGAUGGUUUGUAAAAAGUAUCCUGUUUUUUUAAUUCUAUUCAAAAUUAAAAAUUUUUUUUCCUAAAAUAAAGCAAGAAAAAUAAAUGUAAGAUAUAUAAGAAACCCCAGAGUUUCCAGGGUGAAAGUUCACAUUAGCAGCUUGUCCAAAAUAUUUACACCUCACAAAUAUUUUGAAAGAAACCAUGUUGAAAUUUUCUGAUUUUGUGAGUUACAACCACAGCCCAGUAAAACCAAUACUUGUUAUUUGGCUACUUUCAAGCAAUGCAGAUAUUCUUUAGUAUUUAAAAAUGAGCAAAUAAACAAAAUGAGGCAAAUAAAUGAAGAAAAUGAGUUUCUGAGACACUGUUUAGGUAACCAUAAAUCAGACAGAUAUUUUUAUGGUGGGCAAAUUGAUGAAGAUACUUUUAGUAGGUGAUUUAUAUUCAUAACAAAUACAUAUUGAAAUAAUUGUCACUACUGUAUCAGAAUUAAAAACCAGCUUCACAUUAGGACUUCUCCAUACAAAUGCUUUAUCAUUGGUUCUUAAAUUGGAAAAAUAUCUAUAAAUGAUUACAUUUUUAAGCUAAAUAAAAUGCAGAUAUUUUGGCUUCUUGUGAAUGUAAUAAAGAAUCAUAAAACAUA